GUUAGGGGGCGUUUCUCCAGGAGGAAAGCUGUGAGCUGCGACGCUGAGGAAGGGGACCCCAAAACGUCUGGCACUGCCCCCUCCAGGGAUCACUUUGGACCGCCUCACUCGGGCCAGCCGGAUUCUGAAACGCCGAGGGGUCAACCUGAUGGGUUUCGGGGUCAACGGAAGAGGGGAAGGGGAGCCCUGGCGGGGAGAACCCCCCGGUCCCCCGCCCAGCAGCUGAGGCACAGGAGGGCGGCCAUCUUGGCCGGGAGGGUAGGGCUGGGGAGCUGCGGGCGCCGUGCGAUUGGGGGGCUCGCCCGGAAGUGACGCCAACUACCCGGAAGCGGAGGGGGUUCCCUGGCCCACUCCCCCCUCGUUCGUUUGCUCCCCCGCUUCCUCCCCGCCCCCCUUCCUCUCCAUUCGUUUCCCCCCCUCCCCGUUCCCUGCCUUCUUCCCCCCCCCCCCGCCGUCCCUCCCCCCCAACCUCCGGAGCUGGGAAGAGAGUCAAGAUGGCGGCGAAAUCCGAUGGCGGUGGCGUGGGGGUGGGCUUCGCUCAGCUGCACAACCUGGACGAGGCGGUGGGCAGCGGCGGCGAGGAGGACGGGGAGCCCGGGGGAGGCGGCUGCGGCGGCGGCGGCGACGGCAGCGAGCCCGGCGAGAGCAGCUCGAUGCACAUCUGCCACUGCUGCAACACCUCCUCGUGCUACUGGGGCUGCCGCUCCGCCUGCCUGCGCUCCCUCCUGGGCAGGAAGCCGCGCCGCAGCGCCGCCGCCGACGGGGGGGACCAGCCGCUGCAGCCUCCCGCGGCCCCCGGCGCCGGCCGCCAACCCCCGACGCCCUCGGCCGCGCGGCCGGAGCCGCCGCCGCCGCAGGUGGAGCGGCCGUGGCUCGACUGCCUGUGGAUCGUGCUGGCGCUGCUGGUGUUCUUCGGGGACGUGGGCACCGACCUGUGGCUGGCCCUCGACUACUACCGCAAGGGGGACUACGUCUACUUCGGGCUGACCCUCUUCUUCGUGCUGGUGCCGUCGCUGCUGGUGCAGAGCCUGAGCUUCCGCUGGUUCGUGCAGGACUACACGGGCGGCGGGCUGGGCGCCGUGGAGGGGCUCACCAGCCGGGGCCCCCCCAUGAUGGGGGCCGGCUACGUCCACGGCGCGGCCCGCGGUGGCCCAGGCGUGAGGGUCUCCCCCACGCCGGGGGCGCAGCGCCUGUGUCGCCUCUCCGUGUGGAUCUGGCAGUCGGUCAUCCACCUGCUGCAGAUGGGGCAGGUGUGGAGUGGGCAAGACCCUUUGGUACCAUCAAGGAAAAGAAGGAGCAGAUUUAACCACAUGAAGUUGCCUCACCUGGUUUCUUCCCUUCUCCCUCCUCCCAUCUGAAAAAUCCAGAAAUACUUGCUUAGCUGUGAGGGUAAGUGGGUUAAAUUGAGACAGAGAUACUUCCUCCAGGAGAAUGAAUAAGAAGAGAACAUCUCUAAAGAUUUAUUUCUUGUUUUUGAGUGAACAGUAACCCUAAAAACUUGACAUUUAUGGUAAAUUUUCAAGGGAAGGGGAUGAAAAAAUGGCAUGCUUUGGAGCGAAAUUGCAACUGGGGAUGCAGCAUAGUAUUUCCAGAAGGAUCCAGAAACAAAGUGUCAAAAUCUGUAUUGUAAGAAGGCUGGUGCUCCUGAAAUCUAGCAGGCAGGUGCUUACUAGAAGUCACAAGUUGUUCAUUUCUGUCUUCAACAUCAUUUGAUACUAUAGACUUAUUCAUAAGGUCAAUUGCCUAGUCAGGCUUAUGCAGUGCAGUGGAUAGAUUCUGUAAUGUUGGAAAGAUUCUGUGGGAUGGAAAGAUUCUGUGGGAUGCAAAAAGAAACUGUGUCUCUGAUGUUGCCAUUUUCACCCCAGGAUGAUUUGCUUUACAACGUGCUGUCUGCAAAUAAGUUUGUGGUUAAAAUUUUAGUUUACUCCCCAUGAUGUGCUAUUCAUCUAGUUUCUUCUCAUCAGGAAUUCUGGAUUUCUUAUUUGCCUCUUAAAAAGUAAAACUUUUAAAAAAUUUAUGAAAAUAUAACCUCAUUUAACAAGUUCAUUGACUUUUGACUAAUUGCCUAAAGACAAUCCACUGCUUACCGCUAUUGGAGAUACUUAAGAAAAGCGCAGGACAUAGCCUGGUAUGAAGGGAAUGACUGGUGGAAUUAAGAAGUCAGGUUUCUCACUCUGCAAGUUACAAACAACCACUGGCCUCAGUUUCCUCAUAUUUAUCAAACAAGCAGUUAAAUGGAUUGAUCUUUAAUGUCCCUUCAGUGUAAAAAAGUUCAUUAUGCUACAGGUAUUUGUGCUUUGAAAAUAGCUUUAAAGAGGGAAUUUCAGAUUCUGGUUUGAUCACUUAAUCUAUUUUUAAAGCAAGUGUGUAUGUCUCCUAGGUGCUGAUUCGGAGUAGAGUUCUAAGUCCUGCCAUGGAUUGUUUUGACUUAUUAAACAAAUUCUCAUUUUGUGUCACCUAUGUAUAGGGACAUUUUGGAGAUCUCAUUAGUUAAUGUUAAAAUUUAUGGCAGACUAAACCUACUGAGAAACUUGUGCUGACUUUAUCAGCUAAUUUUGUGAAUUUGCAAUUUCAGCUAAAAUUAAACUAUAUUUUUCAGUAGUCUUUUUUUUGUAAUCUGUUUAAAAUUUUUAGUGGUAGAUUAAGCUAAAGCAAUAUAUGCGUAUCUGUUUAAGCCAAGUAUUUUGGAGGUUUUUCUGAAUUGUUUACCAAGGUUAAUUUCUUUUGUGGGGGGGGGGGGGUCAGAACCUUAAAAUUACCUGCUGUAAUUUGUUGUUUGAGAUGUGUUCUUUAACUUUGAAAAGUUAGUGUUUGUAAAAAAAAAAUUUUUUUAGUGAUACCAUCAGGUCACUUGAGCUCUUUUAGGAAAUAAUUCUGUUAAGUGAAUUUUUUUGUUUGUUUAGAUUAAGGUAUAAGUUCUCUUUUGACACUAGUCGAAUUUUUAGGAAAGAUGGAAUUUGCUGAGAGAAUUCAGUGGCUAUUGUUACAGUGACAUUAAUAUAGUUCUACAUAAAAUUCUACAUGAGAUUUUUCAUUUCUGUAUUUCUAAUGUGGGUAGAUCUUGGUAUAUUGUAUUAUUUUAAUAUAGCUCAAAACAUACUACAGCACCCUAUGGUAUUUUACAGAUUUCUAACAAAAAAUUUCUUCUCAUUGACCUCUUUUACUUUUGAAAUAUUAAACAAGUGGUUUAAAAAAUAAUUUUUGUUUUGAAUGGAGUGUUUUUGUCUUCUUAGUUUAAAUGAGGAAGCAAUUUCUGUUUUAUCUUGGUCACUGAUUUAGAGCAUGGACUGUGCUCAUCAUUCAUUUCUAGGAAGAAAUUAGAGUAUUCAUUUCACAGAGAGCUACAUAUUGUUUUCUUCACCACCCUCUUGGAGGAAAGGUAGGGUUGAUAAUUACGGUUUGCCCUGGCCACAUGCUUUCACUCAUGGGUAGGUGAGCUAAAACAUUCAUAUCACCAUGAUGCUUCCUUUUCUUUCCGUCUUAAAUAGACAGGACAAAUGAGGAAAGGCAGCAGAUUUGAGGAAGAUGCCAAACCCAUGGCUUGGGAAGCUUGCCAGUGAAGUUGAGCAGGCAGGGCAAUCUAGAACUCAGGCCCCUCCAGAGGGCAGGUGCCUGACUUUCUCACUUCAGCUGUGUUUCUUCAAGUGUGGCAGAGACUCCUGUGUUAGGAGAGCCCACGGGGCCAUUAACAUGCGGAUUCCAGGCCUUACUACAGACUCCAGGAUCAGAGCCUCAGGGAGUUGGGCCAGGGAGUGUGUAUUUUUGCUCAAUUUUUAUUAUUGAAGCUUUGAAGCACACAGGGAAAUAGAGCAGUAUAAUGAACACCUGUUACCAUUCACUUGGCUUCAGUAAUUUUUUUUCUAAAGAAACAGAUUCUCACUCUGUUUCCCAGGCUGGAGUGCAGUGGCGUGAGUAUAGCCCCCUGCAGCCUUGAACUUCUAGGCUCAAGCAGUUCCCUUGCCUAUGCCUCCUGAGUAGCUGGGGCUUGAGGCGUGUGCCACCAUGCUUUACUCGUUUAAAAAGAUUUUUGUAGGCCAGGCGCUGUGGCUCACGUCUGUAAUCCCAGCACUUUGGAGGCUGAGGUGGAUGGAUCACGAGGUCAGGAGAUCGAGACCAUCCUGGCUAACAUGGUGUCUCUAUUAAAAAUACAAAAAUUAGCCGGGCGUGGUGGCACGCGCCUGUAGUCCCAGCUACUCAGGAGGCUGAGGCAGCAGAAUCGCUUGAACCCGGGAGGCGGAGGUUGCAGUGAGCCCAGAUCGUGCCACUGCACUGCAGCCUCAGUGACAGAGCGAGACUCCACCUCACAAAAAAAAAAAAUUUUUUUUGUAGAGAUGGGGUCUUGCUAUAUUGCCCAGGCUGGUUUUGAACUCUUGGCCUCAAUCAGUCCUCCUGCCUUGUCCUCCCAAGGAUUAUAGGCGUGAGUCGCUGUGCCUGGCCAGUUGUUAAUAUAGAUAUAUUUAUCUGUAUGUGUGUGUAUUUAACACAUAUCCUAUCCUGAUGUUGCACCUCUAAAUACUUCACCUCAAAUAUGAAAUGUUUAGAAUCAUUCUACAAAGCUACAAUAUUAUUAUUGCACCUAAGAAAAUUAAGAGUAUUUCCAUAAUUAUCCUUAAUUCGUAAAAUCAUCUAAUAGCUGUUUUGUACUCAGAUUUGCCUAGUUGUCCCCAGCAAAUUUGCUUGUGGGUUUUUUCUCCCCUCCAAUCAGGGACUUGAUAAAAAUUUAUGAAUUAUAUUGCUGUUUCUUUAGAAUAGUCCCUCUCUGUUUUUUUUUUUUUUUUCUCAUGACAUUGACUUUUUUCCAGUGUCCUGUCCAUUUCUCUUGUCUGCUCAUAUUUUGCGUUUCCUGAGUGUCUCUUGCAGGUGUCGUUUGCACUCUGUAUUUCUAGUAAACUUGAAGUUGCAUCUAGGGGCUGAAUUACAUUCAGGCACAAAUUUUUGUCAGAAGUACUGCUUUCUUCAUGUUGGCAUCAUAUCAGUAGGCGCCCCAUACGUGUUUUGUCCCACUAUUAGUGAUGCUAAGUUUUAUCCCUUGGUUAAGGUUGCGACUGCCAGAUUUCUUUAUAUAAAGGUAGUUUUUCCCUUGGCAAUCGGUAGGUAACUUGUGGGGUCAUAUGUUAGCAAAGUAUCAGUGUCUCUUUUCCUAAAUACCGUUUACCUUAUGGUUUUAGUGUCUUUUGGGAAUCCUUGCCGGAAUCAAUUAUUAAGUAGUUGUUGUUGGUGGGUGUAUGUGUUUUAAACAGGCUCCCUGGUAAUUCUAACCUUUAAGGUUUGAUAGCCACUGCUGUCCUAUUAAUAGAACUAGGAGCUGAGUUAUCAGGUCUGUUGAAUGGGUUGCCAGUAAACAGUUAAUGAGUUUAAGCUUCGUGUUCAUUUUAGAGAAACUAAGAUCAAUAAAGUGCCUCCUAAGGCCCCCUAUGUCCUAGUUUAGUUGUUGGAGAGGACAUGUGUGUGAUACUUGCAGUAAACUUGAGGUGAGCCCUGCUAGUGUGUUAGAAUGUAUGACAAAAAUCCAAGGAGAGUGGAGGAGGCGUAGAGAAAUUACUAAGGAGGAAAGGAAACUAUAUUGAAUAUUCUGUUUAUAUAUAUAGUCUCACUUAAUUUUCACAAGCAUUUUGUGCCCAUUUUACAGAUGAAGAAGUGAGCUUAAAGUGAUAAAGUAACCUAUGGCACUGGUGGAGGAAACUUUUGAAGCCAGAGCUCACAGAGCUGUGGGCGGGACAGAAUUAGUUUGCUUUACCUCUGGGACGUUGUUGUCUGGCUUAUUGAAGAUGGAGGAAUGAUAUUCUUCAACCUCUGGGGCCUCUUGGUAUAUAAGCUGAGGUUCUUUGAGACCUCUGAUGUCUAGUCUAAUGUGUUAAUAUUAAACUCUGCAGAGCUUAGGGUAGGCUUGUAAGUCUUGUAGUUGAUUGUAACUGCUGAUGAAUCAAACAGCUGAGUAAUAUUAAUACCUCUGGGUCUGUGUCUUAGGACACAGUUUUCAGUACCUCACUCCAUUCUCUUUCUCAGGGUAGAUGCACCUUACAACCCCGUGACUUCCACAUUACACAAAGGAAUAUGUAGGUUUGGCAUACCCCACAGGUCCCAUGUAAAUACUGCACUCAAAUAUGUUGGUUCUCUGUUGACCUGUUGGAAACAUUGAGAACAGCAGUUGUAUCCCAAGGAUAUAAAGAAGCUGUUUUCUUUUCUUUUCUUUUAUUUUCCUUUCUUUUCUUUUCCUUUCCUUUCUUUUCUUUUCUUUUUUCUUUUUUCUUUUCUCUUUCUUUCUUUCUUUCUUUUCUUUCUUUCUUUCUUUCUUUUCUUUCUUUUCUUUCUUUCUUUUUUUUUGGGACAGUUUCACUCUUGUUGCCCAGGCUGGAGUGCGGUGGCGCGAUCUCGGCUCACUGCAACCUCUGCCUCCUGAGUUCAAGUGAUUCUUCUGCCUCAGCCUCCCACGUAGCUGGGAUUACAGGCAUGAGCCACCAUACCCGUCUAAUUUUUGUACUUUUAGUAGAGAAAGUGUUUCACCAUGUUGGUCAGGCUGGUCUCGAACUGCUGACCUCAGGUGAUCUGCCCUCCUUGGCCUCCCAAAGUGCUGGGAUUACAGGCGUGAGCCACUGCACCCGUCCAAAGCAGCUGUUUUCAAACCUUGGCUGUGCAUCAGAAUCACUUGAGGAGCCAGAUAUUUGAGAUCUACCAUAAGAGACUGUAAUCCAAGAGAUCUGGGAUGGGCCCAAGAAUCUAUAUAUUUAAAAAAUCUAGGUUUUCAGAAAGUUCCCUAAGCAGUACACAGACAGGGAUGAGAAGCAUAGUUGUACAGGCUGAUUUCUGCCAAUAUCUAUGAGUUAGUUAUCAAGGAGAAGGAGCAUAUGUUAGAAUUGCUUGGGAAUUUGUUUUUUGUUUUUGGUAAACUUUUUAUCACUAGGCAUCUUAGAUUUAGAGGGGCGGAAUGGAUAAAAGAAGGUCCUCAGGUGAUUCUAAUGGAUUACCAGUAUUUAAACAAUCUGAAUGGACCUUUUAGCUGGAGUGGCUUGGCAAAAAGUCUGUAUUAACCAAAGAGUUGCUGUUGCCAUAUAUUAUGCCUGGAUUUAGAAUGCAGGAAAGACAUUUAACAUUAAAAUUAUGACAUAUAAUUGAGGAUUCCUUUGAUCCAAAAGCUUCUUUCUUUGGAAGUUUGAAGUAUUUCAAGGUCAUUAUUAUGAACACAGAUGAUCCCCAUUGGUGCUCAGAAGUGCCAGGUUAGAGGCAUUUUAUUAUGCUUGGAAAUUGAUAUUUCAAUCCAGUGAAUUUUGUGUCUCAAAUUCAGAAAUGUUAUAUUUGUUGUAAUCAGUGCCAAGGAUAAGAUUCCUAAAAAGAAACUGGUGAAUGAAAGAGGAGACAUGACCUAAUAGAUACUGAGUGUCAUUAGAGACAGGAAAGAAGGGAGCAGAGAAGAAAAAUGGCCUACCUACAUUUUGCUUGAUAGAUUCGUGGGGAGAACAGCCAGGAGAGGGGAUGAGGGGGAGUUGGAUGGUGUUUACUGGUAAGAUAUUAGUGUGGCACAUCAGCAAGCAUCCCUGCAUCUGUGCACACUCAAUACCUUCCCUUUGCACUCCACCUAGAAAUGUACAUGGGGAUGGUGAGAAAAUCCGAGAACCUUGUAACGGAGAAGCUCAGGGCCAGAAAUCCUAGGAGAGGCUGGGCUGGCAGAGGUGGGGCCUGGGGUCUGUGGACUUGCACAGGGCAGGGAGGGUUAGAUCCUCUGCUCGUUGGUGAUUCCGCAUCAAAAUGAGCAGAACUCCAAAUCUGUCAUUUUGUUUGGUCAUAAGGAAGACAGCUUUUGAGUAGUCAACAGAAGAGUUAAUAAAUCACCCUACACUGUACAUUUAAAAGAUGCCACUUUGCCUUCAAAGCUGAAGAAAACUCUGAAGGAAAAGAUGAUGUCUUCCAAAAAGGAAUUCUGUGUUCAAAGUUUAAGCAAUCAAGUGGUUUUGGUUGGGCCUAGAGGGUGAUGGUAUAUAUGGCUGUGGGUUGGAAGGGAAGAGAAACUACAAUAAAGGACUCAUUACUCAGUUUGCAGAUGAAACAAAAGUUGUCAAAACGAAGCUGAAGUUAGAGACAAUCACAUGAUGAGUUUGGAAAAACAGAAUUUGAAUGUGUUUGUAGCAUUUGUGGACUGUGUUUGGGGCGUCCACUAUUUGAUAGGAACUGCAUACUAAUUUUUAGGUAGUUUCUGAGCUGUAAUGUGGGAAAGGGUUGGUGUGUACCCAAGCAGGCCUUUAUGAUUAAAUGUGAUAUGUGUCAGGCAUGUUACCUGGUUUUGGAUGGGGUCUGAUGAGGUUGAAGUGUAUUUUUUUGCUUAUUGCUUGGCAUUUCAACUCACUAUCUCAAAUUAGCGAUGGGCUCAUACCUACUGUAAUGUGAUACACACAUUCCUGAAAAACCUCUCAUUCUGCAAAAUCAUACACUAAAAAUAACAGGGCUGUAGAAAAAAAAACAGGAUUAAGGCCAGACUACUUAAAACUAUGUAACUUUGUAAGUGGAACUUUAACAAAAGCAAUGACAGUUGAAGUAAAAAUACAGGGAGGCUUAACUCUUCCUUGAAACUUGCGCUCAGCAUUAUACUCAGAUGAUUGUAGGGGCCUUAUUUUAUCCUGGGACAUGUUCAUCCUGGGUUAUGUAGAUUCAUUCUUGGAGAUGUUAGUUUAUUCUGCAGGCCAGUUUCACUAGAAUUAAAGCUCUGUUUCAGAGUGUAGCCUUCAUGUGCCCCCACACCAUCAUUGAGUGAUGGAGAGCCCAGCAGAUACUGAGGUGACUAAACCAGCCACCCCCAUGCCCACUGCUUGCACAAAAGGAAGGUGCUUUGAUAUGACUGAUUUUUCUUAGGGUUGUUUUCUUUUUUGUUGUUUUUUUCUAAGUCUUUCUCAUUAUUUGUGAAAAAAUCUUGGCCCUCAAUAGCUUCAAAACGUUAACAUGCUGGGAAGAACCACUCGUGAACCAACACUCCUUCUCCAUGAUACUGUUGUCAUUCCCAUUUUGCCAGUCAUGUGGGAAGGAAUCCAUGUCCCGGAGACAUGUGUUGCAGCAGUUCUGACAUGUUUUUGAAUCAGCGAUGGUGUCACGAUGCAGCUUUUGAGAAUGUCAAGUUUCAGUUGCAUUGGGAAGUUCUUGUUUGGGAGAUAUCCUAUAGUGUUUCAAGGUUAAGUGACAUUUCUUACCUUUCUUAUGCUUUGUUGGCCCUUGUCUACAAUAAAGAACUGAAGUGGAGCUAUUUUUGUCCACUUUUACAUUCUGCCUCCAAAACCUAGCCAUAGGGUGGGAUGCUAUAAUUUCUUGAUGCAGCAUUGGUAUUUGAACAACACACAUGAAGCAGGAAUGGUUUUACAUUUUGGUUCAUUUGAAAUAUGGUUAUAGUGAGGUUUUAAAUAAAUCAUCUGAGCUACAGUAAACAAAAAAAGAGCAACACUAGCCAGUUGUCAAGGAAAAGACUGAUGGGUAGAAUAAACAGACUGCUUUCUGCAGUCUAAACAAUCUGUUUUCAUGGUUUUUUUCUCUUUCUUUUUGAAGGGUGAUUGGGAGAACUUCCAAAUUAAGUAGAAGUUAGUUAAAUAUGAGAGGCAGUAAAUCCACAAUGCGUAUGUUAGUGAUUAUUACAGCCUGUUUUCUCAAUAGCUCUAAUAACAACAAUGUCAGUGACUGAACACAGUAGAACAGUAUUGUUUGUCGUGGGGUGGUAUGGCUGGUGGUGGCUUCGACAUCCUCAGGGCUCAACACCUCAGCAUUCAGUCAGAGAAAGGAAAGAAAGUAUAGAGAAAGUAUAACUGUUUCUUAAAAACUCUAGCUUGGGCCAGGCGUGGUGUCUCAUGCCUGUAAUCUCACCACUUUGCAAGGCCAAGGUGGGAAGAUCACUUGAGUCCAGGAGUUUGAGACCAACCUGGGCAAUGUAGGCAGACCCUGUCUCUACAAAAAUUAAAAAUAGAUGAGCUGGAUGUGGUGUGGCACACCUGUGGUUCCCAGCUAGUUGGGAGGCUGAGAUGGGAAGACUACUUGAGCCCAGGAGGUUGAGGCUGCAGGGGCCUGUGAUUGUGCCACUGCAGCCUGGAUAACGGAGCAAGACUCUCUCUCUGUCUCUCAAAGCCCUGGUUUGAAGUGAAGUGAAACACAUCACUUCCACUCACAUGCCAUUGUGAAGAACUAGCCGUGGACCAUACCUAGAUCAAGGGUGGCUGGGCAACACCUUCACAUCACAGGAGAGGUAGACUGCAUUUUGGUGGAUAGAGACUCAAAGAAUUCUGUGUAGAUCAGGUACCUUCCAGAUUAAAGUGGGAUGGGGAUGGGGGGGCAUGAAUGUGUCUAUGUGUGUGUAUGUAUAAAAAAAAAUGCUAUUGAUUGCAGAGUACAAGAGACGAUUUCCCUUUAAAACUUUGAUUUCUGUUUUGAUUCGGGACUUGGCAAGCUUUUUCUGUAAAGAAGUAUUUUAAGAUGUGUAGCCACAGAAGGCCUCUGAUGCACAGUCCCCUCGAAAAAUAUAAAAAGCAUUCUUAGUCUGAGGGUGGUACAGAAAUAGCCCAAGCCCUGUUUCCAUCGAUCAGCUCAAACAGGUAACUAUUUAAAUUAGCUUUUAAAAAUAGUUGUGAAGUUUAAUGAAGAGUGAGUCAUACUAAAUACACUAAACUAUCUUGAAAUUAUACAACUGGAGUUUUAAAUAAUUUUUCUUUAGAUGAUAUUUCAUUGAGGUAAAAAUGGCCUUCAGGGACUCAAUGAAAAGUAUUGUAGCCAUGUGCCCAAGACUCAUCAGUGUUUCAGGUCUUAAGGAAAAGUUCAUCUGGUUGAGGAAAGAUUGGAUCUUGGUUUGUGAGCACAGCUAAUGUACUCUUUCAAAAUCAUGUCCCAUCAUUGGAGACUUUAUUGGGUGCCAUCUCCCAGGAAACUAUCCCUAAAAGUGACUACUGAUUCUCAUCUGUUGAAUAUAUAGAUCACCAAAUAGAUAUUUAAAAAAUGUGAAAAAUUGUACGUACAUUUAGAAAUUUACUCUAAAACCCCAUACAGUAAAUCUUCACUGUCAUCAGUGAGUUCUUAGAAACUGCAAUUUGAAGUGAAACUACGUAUAUGGAAACCAGUUUUCCCAUAGGCUAAUUGAUACAAACAAGAUUAAGUUUCUGUGGCAUAUUUCUGUUCACAAAAACACCACCAAACUUUUAAGUAAAGACCAAAACACUUCUAGCAUUAAACGUUGAAAUAAAUGUGAGCCAUACCUAUAUUUAAGAAAGAUUAAUGCAACGUGAGAUAAUUCUUACCCACUUAUUCCACCUGGUCACAGGUGGUCAGAGCCUAUCCUAGGAGCUCAGGGCACACGGCGGGCACCAGUCCUGGACAGGGUGCCAUCCCAUCACAGGGCACACUCACACUCACACCCGCACCCAUGUCCUUAGACUGGGACCAGGUAAAUGCGUUAAUAAACCUAAUGUGCCCAGCUUUGUCUGGGAGGAAACCCAGGUACCCAGAGAGAAAAACCACCAGACAGUGGCCCGGUUGGGAAUGGAUUUUUCUUAUCAACUGUGUAACUAAAUGAUGGUCAAUGAAACGAUGUUAUUUGAGGAUGUGCUGUAUACUAAAAUAUAUGGAAUUCUAUUUGGUUUGUGUGUUAGUAACCCCUGGGGAUGGAUUCAGAUGAUCUGAAAAUUCCUUAUUGAGGCUGUGCAUGGUGGCUCACACCUGUAUUCCCAGCACUUUGGGAGGCUGAGGCGGGUUGAUUGCAUGAGCCCAGGAGUUUGAGACCAGCCUGGACAACAUAGUGAAUUCCCGUAUCUACAAAAGUGAAAAAAAACUAUAGAAAUUCCUUAUAAAGGUGUUAAAUAUCUAAAUAUGACUUAAAUGUAAAACCAAACCAGAAAUGUUUUCAUCGAAACAGGUCAGUAUGUUUUGUAAGUUCUUAUAGAAAACCAUAAAAUAUUUAAAAAACAGAAAUCUACCAUUCUAGCCUUGAAGUUUCUAACAGUCAGCUGUCUUAAAAUACCUGUUCAGUUAGUUCCAAGUGUUAAGUUACAUUUUCUGACAUUCUUAAUGGGCUUUUAAAAAUUAGGUUACUAAUAAAUGUAAUAUAAGUGUGUGUGUGUGUGUGUGUGUGUGUGUGUGUAUGUGUGUAUAUAUAUAUAUAAAAUAUGUAUUUAUUUAGAGGCUAUUUAAUAAUUUAAAAGCUCCUUUACAUAGUAUCUCCACCAGUUGAGACUGUACCAGGGGUCUGCAUGAGGGCUCUUGUUUCUUCUUAAAAAGCCAAAAUCUGUGACCUGUGUGGCUAAUAAGUAAUUAUUAUCUUCUCAGACUAUUGUACUUGAGAGAUUAAACUGCAAAUUAUAAUUAGAAUAAAACUAUACUCUGAAACCUUUAACAGUCUCUGUAUGGUGGUAGAGGUCAAAUAUACACUAUGUAUGAGAUAAUUUUUUUGUCUAGCUGAUCUUAUUAAUAGAGUUUUAACACUUUUCGUUAUAUUUGCUUAUAUUAUCUGGUGCCGGCUCAGUCUUGCCCUUACAGUGGAAUCAUCUGUUGUAGCCGGGGGAUAUUAUUGCCCAGACUACAGACAGUCCUGACUUGUUGGCAUUGUAUAAAGCAUGCUCCAGAUAAACACUACUAUGUACAUUGCUUCCAAAAGUUCAUAGUACUGCAAAUGUUAUAACCCUUAUGCUGUGUUUAAACCCUUAUUCCUGAGCCUUUCCGCUUCAUGAGCCCACUUGGCCAGACUUUCCAAAAACCGUAUUUAGGGGCCUUAUAGUAAUAUUAAUCAACACAGAUCUUAGGACCUCUUUUCAAGAUCAAAUAAAAAAUGAAUUGGUUAACCUCACAUUGUAGUUUAUUUUGACUAGCACAGAUGUAAUCUUAAAUAAUUUUUAAAAAUCCAGAAAAUAAGCCAGGUGUGCUGGCUCAUACCUGUAAUCCCAGCACUUUGGGAUGCUGAGGUGGGAGGAUCACUUGAGGCCAGGAGUUCAAGACCAGCUUGAGCCCAGCAUGGUGGGACCCUAUGUCUUCAAAAAGUUAAAAAAAAAAAAAAACUAGACAGGUGUGGUGGCGCAUGCCUGUAGUCCCAUCUACUUGAGAGGCUAAGGAAGAGAAUCACUGGAGCCCAGGACUUUGAGGCUGCAGUGAGCUACACAAGACAAUAAGUGCUAACAGGUAUGUGGAGAAAUUGGAACCCUUGUGCAAUGAUGAUAGGAAUGUGGAAUGGGGCAGCUGCUGUGGAAAGCAAUAUAAUGAUUCUUCAAAAAAGUAAACAUGGAAUUACCACAUGAUCCAGCAGUUUCAAUUCGGGCUGUAUAUCCAAAAGAAAGGAGGGUCUCAAGGAGAUAUUUGUACAGCCACAUUCAUAGCAGCACUAUUCACAGUAACCAAAAGUGGAAGCAACCUAAGCCUUCAUCAACACAAGUGAAUAAACAAAAUGGAUACAAGACGCAUUCAAAGGAAUGUUUCAGCCUCAAAAAAAAGGCAAUUCUAACACAUGCUGCAACAUGGAUGAACCUGGAGGACAUUCUGCAAAGUGAAAUAAGGCCACCAUAAAAGGACAAACACUAUGUGAUUCCACUUACAAAAGGGCCGUGGAGGAGUCAAGUUCAUAGAGACAUAGUAGAAAGGGGGCUGCCAGGGGCUGGGGCGAGGGGAUACGUGGAGUUACUGUUAAUAUGGCACAGAGUUCCAGUUUUACAAGAUAAAAACUUGCAGAAAUGACUGAUGAUGCAUUGUGAAUGUAUUUAAUGCCACUGAACUGUACACUUGAAAAUGGCUCAGAUGGUAAAUUUUGUUGUAUAUACUUUGCCACAAUUAAAACAAUUUUUACAAAUA